CCCUAGUGGCAGCAGCGCCUUGUACUUAAAAAUAGAAUACUACCAACAUCAUCUUCCUUCCCAGGAUGACAAGGCAUUGAGAAAAUUAGAAUGUGUAUAUUUUCUCCCUUUUUUUUUUUUGAGACAGUCUCACUCUGUCCCCCAGGCUGGAGUACAGUGGCGCGAUCUCAGCUCAUUGCAACCUCCGCCUCCCGGGUUCAAGCGAUUCUCCUGCCUCAGCCUCUCGAGUAGCUGGGAUUACAGGCCCGUGCCACCAAGCCCAGCUAAUUUUUGUAGUUUCAGUAGAGACGGGGUUUCACCAUGUUGGCCAGGCUGGUCUCGAAUUCCUGACCUCGUGAGCCACCGUGCCCGGCCUCUCCAUUUUCUAAGACAUGCGUUUUUUCAUUUGUACAUACGUAUCUUAGCAUUGAUACCCCCUCUACAUUUGUUUAUAAAACAGUGGUACAUCUUGUAAUCAGUAGCUUCUUAGAACUGAGGAAUUCGUUUUGUCAUCACUCUGAAGGGCAGUUUAGCCAGUACAGUAAGUCUUCACUCCAUAGGUUCUUGGAAAUUGCAAUUUUAAAUGAAUGAGAUAUCAUGAAAGCAAUUUGACCAUAGGCUAAUUGAUAUACAUAAGACUUAAGUUCCUUCCAAAAUACGUACAAUGUUAAACACUGAAAUAAAGGUAAGCUAUACAUACAUUUAAGAAAGAUUAAUUUAAAAACAAGUAAGAUGAUUAUUUAAUCAGUUAUUCCAGCUCGGGGUUUCUGGUGGAUGGAGCCUGUCCCAGCAGCUCAGGGUGCAAGGCAGGGCACCAGCCCUGGACAGGAUGCCAUCCCAUCACAGAGCACAUUCGUACACAGCCAGAGUCACUCAGACUGGGACAGUGUAGACAUGCCACUUUGCCUCAUGUGCACAGCUUUGGGGUGUGGGAGGAACCCUGAGGACCCAGAGAAAACCCACGCGGAUGUGGGGAAAACGUGGAAACUCCACCGAUAGUGGCCAUGGCCAGGAAUCCUUUUUUUUUUCCUCAUUAAUGUUAUAACAAAAUGACAUUGAAUGAAAUGUUAUUCAAGGACCUGCUGUAGUUACAAAUUGGUUAUUAGACGGGUUGAAGUCUCUGCUUGGCCACUUUCUAGCUGACGUUAAGUUUCUCAUCUGACUUAAAAGUCCAGGAAAGACGAAAUGAUAUUAUUUAGCACAGCAGCCUGACUUAUAGUAGAGCAUCAGUACAUAUUACCUAUAGUUGUUUUCAUGAAACUAUUUCACCAGAAGUUUAGGGAUUUAUCCUCAAAGGCAUUAGGAGUGCCUACACGGCACAUAAGGGCAUUGUUUUGUAUCAUACCACAAGUAGCACUUAAGGUUGGAAUCAUUGCUGACCCCAAUGUAAAAUGCCUCUUUCUGGACCAGAAAAUGGAAAGUGAAAUUUGCAAUUCAUCCCAUGUUAUUUAUUUAUUUAGAGACAGAGUCUUGCUGUGUCACCCGGACUAGAGCUGGAGUGCAGUGGUGCAAUCUUGGCUCCCUGCAACCUCUGCCUCCUAGGUUCAAGCGAUUCUCCUGCCUCAGCCUCCCGAGUAGCUGGGACUACUACAGGUGUGCGCUACCACACCUGCUAAUUUUUGUAUUUUUAGUAGAGACAGGGUUUCACCAUGUUGGCCAGGCUGGUCUCAACUCCUGGGCUCCAGUGAUCUGCCUGCAUCGGCCUCUCAAAGUGCCAGGAUUACAGGAGUGAGCAACCAUGCCCGGCCCUCUGUAUUUUUGAUGGGAUGGAUGGUUCAACAUUUAAAGAGAACCUAAAAAGUUAAAAGUAAAAGCAAAGAAGUCUUAAUAACAAAAAGCACCUUCAUGCAAUGUCACUGUUUUACUGCAUCUUAAUAAAGAAAUGUGGCCACCUUAGACCCAGAAUAUAAUCAAUUUUUAAUUGUCUUUCUUGGAUAAUAUCAAGAUAGAGUGUAAUAAGUUAGGUUAACAUAUUAGCUUGCAUCUUGUCAGGGAAAAUAGGUAGAUCCUCUGAACACAGAGGAAGGAGGGACGUCCACGUUUGUCCUGUUUAGUGUCAUACUGAAGAAGAGUAUGACCAGCCAGUGCUGGGCGUUCUGCAGCUUGGGACAGAUGUUGGGGGGAAGGGCACUGCCUUUCUUGUGAACUUUCUUGCCCAAGGGACAAAUGAGCUAAGCAGUACUACGUUAUUAGUGGGAUGUGUAUGUGUGUGUGUGUGUAUGAGAGAGAGAGAGAGAGAAAGAGAAAGAGAACAGAGCCUGUAAGUCUUGCCAUUUUGCCUUUUCAGACAACCCACCCCCACCCCUCAGCAUAGGAAUGUAGUCCUAACCCCAAGCCACUGCUUCUUCUGCUUGCAGCUCUAAACUUGAGCAGGUCUUGGGGGCAGUUCACCAGUGCACCACACUACACUACUCUCAGCAAUCUUUUUUUUUUUUAAACAGUGAUUUGCACUGAUCUAGCCUCUAAGGGGUAAGGGCCGAGAUGAAGCAGAGAAUUUAUUUUUAUAUUAUGUCGUCUGGUGCAGAGACUGCUACAAAAUCAGGAGUCAAAAAUCUAAGGGAAUAGGCUGUGAAGUCAUUUUGUCCAUGAGUUGUGUUACAACACAUUCAUUCAUUGUAAACAAUCACCAACAGUCAUUGCCAUAAUUUAUUCUUGGCAGUAAAUUGGGUUUUCUAGUGACAGAGUAAGCCAUCAGAAUUAAGCAACCAGGAGCUCCAGUUCAUGUGUGCUGGAAAAGAUGUUUGCGAGACUUCAGGUACCACUACCUCAUAUUAAAGGUGAGCAAGUGGAGGCCCAGAGAGGGCAGGUGACUUGCCCAAGGUCACACAGUGGGUUAGAGCCAUAUCAAGGACUAGAACAUUGGUAAUCCAUCACAUCGUCCUUAAACCUUUCUGCCCCACUUCCUGUUGACACAAUAGGCAGGAUAUUAAACUCCAGUUUCAUUCCUGGGGAUUGAUAUGAAAGGUUUUUUACUUGUCCAAUCCCAUUUUCCUUGUCCAGGCAGAUGACAGGUAGUAAUUUCAGAAACUGAGCAAGGGAUGGUGAAAGCUAGAUUGUAGUGGGCUCUUUUUGGUUUGGUUGUUAUGAGCGCUCUCAAUGCAAAGCUUAGAAACCUCUCCAGAGAAAUAAUCAGCUCUCCAAGGAGUGCUCUUGCAGACUAGCAUGUUGCCUUGCUUGCUGGUGUGUAUCUUCCUAUAAAUUCCUGGUAUCCAGUGUCCAUACAGGAGAAAUUGGCUGACUUGUUUUCUUGCUGUGUUGUAUGACAGAUAAUCAGAAAUGUAACUCUGGUGCCUUGUCAUGUGCCCAGAGGAAGUUAAAUGUGCUUGCCUUUAAUAUGUAUAUGUAUACACACACACACACACACAGCAGUUAGAAAAUAGAUGUUUGUAAAAUAUGAUUUUUUUAGGGAAUAUGUAAAAACUGGCAUCUCUUCAGAUAGACAUAGAGGUACUUAAAAACCUUGGUUAAUAUGUCUUGUUUGUAUACUCCAUGUGGUGUAUUUUACACAGUAUCUAAAGGUGUUGCCUGAUUUUGAAUUAGUUAAAAGACAGGUUAGAGACGUGGGAGAAGAGUAUGUUGUAUUUCUUGUCUGAUCUGAGGAAUUUUAUAUUCCUGAAGUCUAUAAUUAGGUGCUUGUGUUGAUUGUUUAUUGAAACAAAGCUGAAGGUGGGGGUGAGGGGAGUGCCACAUAGUGGAAAACACUCUAUGGCAAACAUCUGAGCUUUACUUAAAAGCAUGGGCUGCAAAGAAAUGUAAAUUCAUUGGCUUAAUUGGAAGAGAGUAUUUAUAGAAAUUGAAUGAUCCAGUAAAACUAAAAGCCUGGCUUCUUUCAUCUUCAGAGACCUGCCUUAGUAAAUGCUGUUCUGGAAAUCCCUUGCCUGCAAAGUGGACUUUGCCAUCCAAUUUCUGGCCUCCUGGCAGUCAGUCACUUUGACCUAACCCUAUUGCUUGACUCGUAUUUACUACGUACUUUCCUUUUUUGGCUUAGGGUUGUACUGAAAAUGUACAUGUAAAGAAAAAAAUGUCCAUGUACACUGAAGUUUUCUGAUUUUUUAUAUAGCUCCAUAAUUUGAUUUCAAUAACUAUUACAAAGAAACUUUUAUAAGAAGAUACAAUUUGAAAAUCUUGCUGUGCAGCCUCUUCCCAUCUACUCUGCCUGCCUACUACGCCUUUUAUAGUUCACCAUAUCCAUUAGGUUCUCGAAAAUUCUUCCACUGUUUAUGCAAAUCUUUAAAUUUUUAAAUACUUUUAUUUUCCUUCUUAGAAAAGGUGACAACUAGAUGCUAUUCUGCACCUUGUUUUUACAUGGAAUCAUAUACCUUAAUAAGCUUUUCAGACACUCUUUCAAUCUUCUGCUAUUAUGAAGUUGCAGUGAAUAACCUUGUAUAUCACUUCAUACAUGUGCAGGUAUAUCUGUAGGGUAAUUUCCUAUAAGGGGAUCAGGAUUUGGGCCAGCAGAUAUGUGCAUAUGUAUUUGUGAUCGUGUGGCUAGCCCCUCCUUUUUUUAACUUUUAUUUUAAGUUUAGGGGUACAUCUGCAGGUUUGUUAUAUAGGGAAACUCGUGUCAUGAAGGUUUGUUGUACAGAUUAUUUCAUCACACAGGUAUUAAGCCUAGUACCCAUUAGUUAUUUUUCCUGAUCCUCUCCCUCCUCCCACUCUCCACCUUCUCUGGUAGGCCCCACUGUCUGUUCCCCUUUAUGUGUCCAUAUGUUCUUAUAAUUUAGCUCCCACUUAUAAGUGAGAACAUGCAGUAUAUGGUUUUCCGUUCCUGUGUUAGUUUGCUAAGGAUAAUGGCCUCCAGCUCCAUCCAUGUCCCUGCAAAGAACACAGUCUCAUUAUUUUUAUGGCUGCAUAGUAUUCCGAGGUAUAUAUGUACCACAUUUUCAUUAUCCGGUCUAUCAUUGGUGAGCAUUUAGGUUGAUUCCAUGUCUUUGCUAUUGUGAAUAGUGCUGCAGUGAACAUACGGUAUGCAUGAGUCUUCAUAACAGAACAAUUUAUAUUCCUUUGAGUAUAUACCCAGAAAUGGGAAUGCUGGGUUGAAUGGUAUUUCUGGUAGUUUUUUUGGUCCUUGAGAAAUCGCCACACUGCUUUCCAUAAUGGUUGAACUAAUUUAUACUUCCACCAACAAUGUAUAAGCCUUUUUUUUGGCAACCUCACCAGCAUCUAUUGUUUUUUGAUUGUUUAAUAAUAGACAUUCUGUCUGGUGUGAGAUGGUAUCUCAUUGUGGUUUUGAUUUGCAUUUUUCUAAUGAUCAGUGACAUUGAGCUUUUUUUCAUAUGCUUAUUGGCUGCAUCACAUGUGUGUCUUUUGAAAAGUGUCUGCUCAUGUCCUUUGCCCACGUUUUAAUGGGGCUGUUUGUUUUUUUCUUGUAAAUUUGUUUAAGUUUCUUACCGAUGCUGGAUAUUAGACCUUUGUCAGAUGCAUAGUUUGCAAAAAUUUUCUCCCAUUCUAUAUGUUGUCUGUUUACUCUGUUGAGAGUUUCUUUUGCUGUGCAGAAGCUCUUUAGUUUAAUUAGAUCCCAUUUGUCAAUUUUUGCUUUUGUUCCAAUUGCUUUUGGUGUCUUCGUCAUGAAAUCUUUGCCCGUUCCUGUUUUCAGAAUGGUAUUGCCUUGGUUGUCUUCCCGGGUUUUUAUAAAAGUUUUGGAUUUUACACUUACCUUUAAUCCAUCUUCAGUUGAUUUUUAUAUAUGGUAUAACGAAAGAGUCCACUUUCAAUCUUCUGCAUAUGGCUAGCCAGUUAUCCCAGCACCAUUUAUUGAAUAAGUAGUUCUUUACCCGUUGCUUAAUUUUUGUCAGGUUUGUCGAAGAUCAUAUGGUUGUAGGUGUGCGGCCUUACUUCUGGGCUCUCAUUCUGUCCCAUUGGUCUAUGUGUCUGUUUUUGUACCAGUACCAUGCUGUUUUGGUUACUGUGGCCCUAUAGUAUAGUUUGAAGUCAAGUAGUGUAAUGCCUCCAGCUUUGUUCUUUUUGCUUAGGAUUGCCUUUGCUAUUCAGGCUCUUUUUUGGUUCCAUAUGAAUUUUAAAAUAGUUUUUUCUAGUUCUGUGAAGAAUGUUGUUGGUAGUUUGAUAGGAAUAACAUUGAAUGUGUAAAUUGCUUAUGUUUUCCCAUUUGUUUGUGUCAUCUCUGAUUUCUUUGAAGAGUGUUUUUAAUUCUUGUUGUAGAGAUCUUUCUAGUGUAUUCCUAGGUGUUUUAUUCUUUUUGUGGCAGUUGUGAAUGGGAUUAUGUUUCUGAUUUGGCUCUUGGCUUAACUGUUGGUAUAUGGGAAUGCUAGUGGUUUUUGUAUGUUGCUUUUGUAUCCUGAGACUUCGCUGAAUUUAUGUAUCAGCUUAAGGAGCUUUUGGGCUGAGACUAUGGGGUUUUCUAGAUAUAGAAUCAUGUUGUCUGCAAACAGAGGGUAGUUUGACUUCCUCUCUUUUUAUUUGGAGGCACUUUAUUUCUUUCUCUUGACUGAUUGCUCUGGCCAGGGCUUCCAAUAUUAUGUUGAAUAGGAGUGGUGAGAGAGGGCAUCCUUGUCUUUUGCCAGUUUUCAAGGGGAAUGCUUCCAGCUUUUGCCCAUUCAGUAUUAUGUUGGCUGUGGAUUUGUCAUCGAUGGCUCUUAAUAUUUUGAGGUAUGUUCAUUCAAUAUGUAGUUUACUGAGAAUUUUUAACAUGAAGCAGUGUUGAAUUUUAUUGAAAGCCUUUUCAGCAUCUAUUGAGAUAAUCAUGUGUUUUUUGUCUUUAGUUGUUUAUGUGAUGAAUCACAUUUAUUGCUUUGCCUGUGUUGAACCAACCUUGCAUCCCAGGGAUAAAGCCUACUUGAUCAUGAUGGGUAAGCUUUUUGAUGUGCUAGUGGGUUUGUUUUGCCAGUAUUUUAUUGAGGAUUUUUGCAUAGAUGUUCAUCAAGGAUAUUGGCCUUAUUUUUUCAUUGUGUCUCUGCCAGGUUUCGGUAUAAGGAGGAUGCUAGCCUCAUAGAAUGAGUUGGGGAAGAAUCCCUCCUCCUCAAUUUUUUGGACUAGUUACAGUGGGAAUGGUACCAGCUCUUUGUACGUCUGGUAGAAUUUGGAUUUGGCUGUAAAUCUGUCUGGUCCUGGGCUUUUCUUGGUUGGUAGGCUAUUUAUUGCUGAUUCAAUUUCAGAGUUCAUUAUUGGUCUCUUCAGGGAUUCUGUUUCUUUCUGGUUCACUCUUGGGAGGGUGUAUGUGUCCAGGAAUUUAUCCAUUUCUUUUGGAUUUUAUAGUUCCUGUCGCUUGCCCUUUCAGUGGACUAUUUUUGUUUUUUUAAAUGGAAUGCUUCACAAAUAUGCCCCUUCCUUGCACAGAGGCCAUGCUAAUUUUCUCUGUAUUUUUCCAAUUUUCAUAUAUGUGCUGCUGAAGCGAUCACCCUAAGUACUGUUUGAUUUUUGCACUCCUGUCAACUUAAUUAGGGCUGCACCAAUAGAGUGGGUUAUCAAACUUUUGGAUUUUUGCCAAUCUCAUUUGUAAAAUAUACUUUAUUGAUAUGGUUUAGAUUUGCAUACCUUUUUUAAAAAAGCAAAAGCCUGGACAUCUUUUCAAGAUGUUUAAAGGCCAUUUGUUGGCCAGGUGCGGUGGCUCACACCUGUAAUCCCAGCACUUUGGGAGGCUGAGGAGGGUGGAUCACGAGGUCAGGAGAUCCAGACCAUCCUGGCCAACCAACAUGGUGAAACCCCGUCUCUACUGAAAAUACAAAAAAAUUAGCUGGGCAUGGUGGCACACACCUGUAGUCCCAGCUGCUCAGGAAGCUGAGGCAGGAGAAUCGUUUGAACCCGGGUGGCAGAGGUUGCAGUGAGCCGAGAUCGCACCACUGUACUCCAGCCUGGUGACAGAGUGAGACUCCAUCUCAAAAAAAAAGAAGCCAUUUGUUUUUCUUGUUUCUUUCUUUUUGUUUGUUUGUUUGUUUGUUUGUUUGUUUUGCAAACUGUACUUAAUUCCUGUACGUGAUUUACUCUUCUGUUGGAUUCUUGCUCUUUUUCUUGUUGAUUUGUAAGGGCUCUUUAUAUAAUAGGGAGAUUAGCUCUAAGUCUGUGAUAUGAUCUUCAAAUUUUUCUUGGUUUAUCAUUUCCUUUAGUAUUUGUGGGGUUUUUUUGGUCUUAUACAGAAUUUUCCAUUCUUUCUUUUAUGGCUUCUGGAUUUCGAGUCACAGAAAGCAUUUCCACCAACCCCUUCCACACAUACACGCACAAGAAUUGACCCAUAUUUUCUUGCAGAAUUUCUAUGCUAUUACUUUUUUUACAUUUAAAUAUUUGCUCCAUUUGAGGUUUAUCCUGAUAUUCUGUUAAGUAUGGAUUCAAGUUUUUUGUUUUUGUUUUUGUUUUUGUUUUGGAAAUAGGCUCUCACUCUGUUGCCCAGACUGGAGUGCAGUGGUGCAGUGACGGCUCACUGCAGCCUCGACCUCCUGUGCUCAGGUGAUUCUCUUGCCUCAGCCUCCUGAGUAGCUGGGACCACAGGUGCACACCACCAUGCCUGGCAAAUUUUAUUAUUUGUGGAGACGAGGUCUCGCUACAUUGUCCAGGCUGGUCUCUAACUCCUGGGCUCGGGCGAUCCUACCUCCGCCUCCCAAAGUGCUGAGAUUAUAGGCAGGAGCAGUCGUGCCUGACUCAACUUUAUUUUUUGUAGAUGGCUACCCAAUUUCCCUAACCACUUAGUCAAAAUGCCCACCUUUCCUCCCACUGAAGUGCCACCAUUAUAAAGUAAAUAUUUUGUAAAUGAAAAAUGCCCACUAUUCCCUUGUAAAACAAGAAACUGUGGGUCACCAUUUUUUGGAAAGAAUGUUUCAGUUCUCUUUUUAACUCAAGACAGCUCUUCCACUUUGUCCUCCAAGGAUAAUAUUUACUCCAGAGUGAAUGAAUGAGGUUAACAACCCACCUGCUUGUUUCUCCCUAGUGGAAUGUUAACAUUUUGCCUCUUGGCACAAUUCUCAAGAUUUAUCUUAAGACCCUGUCUCCUUUCACUCAAAGUAUUUGUCUCUUUAUCACAAAGCCUGAAGAAACAUUUCUUGUUACUCAAGGACCAUGCCUUUUAUGAGCCCUAAGAACAGGAGUUAUCAAAGUGUGGUCUUCCCCAGACCAGCAGUCUCAACAUCAGCUGAGAAUUGUCAGAAAUGCAAACUGCUAUCCUUGAGCUACAGAAUCAGAGACCCUGUGUGGACAAGCCCAACAAUCUGAAUUCAACAAGCCUCUCAGGUGUUUCUGAGCAUGCUCAAGAUUGAGACCCAUGACCUUAGAGGCAAAGCGAAGGCUGGAGCUAGGAGAAAGCGGUCAUCAGUACCUCUCAGAUGGUUUAAAAACCCCCAAGGGCAAAGGAAGAGCUGCACUACGAAGUCCAGAUAGUCCAAAAACUCCAAAAUCUCCCUCAGAAAAAACGCGGUAUGAUACGUCUCUUGGUCUGCUCACCAAGAAGUUCAUUCAGCUCCUGAGCCAGUCACCCGAUGGGGUAUUGGAUUUGAACAAGGCAGCAGAAGUGCUAAAAGUGCAAAAGAGAAGGAUUUAUGAUAUCACCAACGUUCUGGAAGGCAUCCACCUCAUUAAGAAGAAGUCUAAAAACAACGUCCAAUGGAUGGGCUGCAGUCUGUCUGAGGAUGGGGGCAUGCUGGCCCAGUGUCAAGGCCUGUCAAAAGAAGUGACCGAGCUCAGUCAGGAAGAGAAGAAAUUAGAUGAACUGAUCCAAAGCUGCACCCUGGACCUCAAACUGUUAACCGAGGAUUCAGAGAAUCAAAGGUUAGCUUAUGUUACAUAUCAAGAUAUUCGAAAAAUUAGUGGCCUUAAAGACCAAACUGUUAUAGUUGUGAAAGCCCCUCCAGAAACAAGACUUGAAGUGCCUGACUCAAUAGAGAGCCUACAAAUACAUUUGGCAAGUACCCAAGGGCCCAUUGAGGUUUACUUAUGUCCAGAAGAGACUGAAACACACAGUCCAAUGAAAACAAACAACCAAGACCACAAUGGGAAUAUCCCUAAACCCGCUUCCAAAGACUUGGCUUCAACCAACUCAGGACAUAGCGAUUGCUCAGUUUCUAUGGGAAACCUUUCUCCUCUGGCCUCCCCAGCCAACCUCUUACAGCAGACUGAGGACCAAAUUCCUUCCAACCUAGAAGGACCGUUUGUGAACUUACUGCCUCCCCUGCUGCAAGAGGACUAUCUCCUGAGCCUCGGGGAGGAGGAAGGCAUCAGCGAUCUCUUCGAUGCUUACGAUUUGGAAAAGCUCCCACUGGUGGAAGACUUCAUGUGUAGUUGAUUAUGCUUCGUGUGAACUCUCCUUAAAAACCGAUAUUUUUUUAUCAUGGAACCAGAACAUCUGUCAUGCAGUGUUGUCCCUUCCUACCUUCUUCCUCCAAGAGAGUAUCAUGAAGUAAACUACAAACUUCAGAAGAAAGCUGACAUUUUAAUGAAUUUUUUAAAAAAUUAAUAAACAAAUUGUCUAAACGCACAGUUGCAGGCUCCCUUGGGAAAGCCCUGCUUUGCUCCAGGCUCCAAGAUCUCCUGGCUAAGUCAGCAAGUGAGAAAAUGUGCAAUCAGGUGUCUCUCACCCCGAAUUGUCCUUCCUCCUUCCUCCCCGGAUUGGCUUGCUGUGCCUGACGGAUGGGCUGUAGAAUGGGGUCUGGCCACCUGGCCUGCUGGGAAACAGCAAUCUUCCUUAAUAGCAUUUCAAGCCGUGCCUUCUCCGCAGAAUGCAUGUCUUUGAGGUCUGCUAAUAUGGAAUGGAACUGCAGCAAAUGCAAACUUGAAGUCAUGCAAAAGUAUGAAAUGGAUUUCUUCAGCUCUUCUUAGGAAUAUUUAAAUUACUGUCAUAAUUCAGUUUAAGCUAUGAACUGUGUGUCCCAGUAGGAGGUCAAGAAAACCUCCACAGCCUUCUGGAUGAAGAACCUGUUUUCAAAUAUACUUGUUGCAGAUACAGAAGACUAGUAGAGUUCUGCCACUCUAAGCUGUUGUGGAUUUUCCUGUCUCCAUGAACCACUCCCAUUCCCCCGUCCCCAAUGUGUUUGUGAGUUUCCAGUUGAUUUGUAGCAAAUGCCUACUUAGUUCUUUGUGGAUUGUUCUAGACUUUUAAUUUUUUUAGCUGCCAUUUAAGCAUUCCUGUGGCACCCAUCACCAUUUCAAUUUAAUUGUUUACUUUGAAGCGGUUUUUGCAAAUUCAUAUUACUUAAGCAGAGGGAGAGAACCUCUACUGAUCAGAGCAUCUAAACCUGUGUGAUCUAAGGUUUAUCAGCCUCUGCAAGGAGCUUUGUCCCAUCGUGCUUCCAUUCCCAGGAGGGGGAGCUUGGAGCGAGUCAGUCCUGGGGCUUGCUGACAUGGGUGGCCCAUUGGAAAGGAGAACCAGGUCAGAUGAUGUAACAGCCCCAAGGAGCAGCAGGCAUGGGUCCCUCCAUCCUUGGGCUUCCCGGGCCCCUGUGACAGGGGAAAGGGCUCUCUUACACCGCACUCAGGGAGACCACUUCUCAGGAUGGGGUCAGAUGGAGAGACCUCUAGGGAGAAAGACAUCCCCAUUGUGUGAGUGGCAUUUCCUUAAGCUGGCAGGAACAGGGAGCAGCCCUGUGUCGGGGGCUGGAAUAGUUCUGGCCAGACCCCGUUCCCCUUCCUCUAUGAAGGAAUAAGUUGGACCAAGGGAAGUCGGGGACGUAAAAAAUGAAGCAAAACAAUGCCAGGGUGUCUCCCGCUUUACUCUUCAGGAAUGGUGUCCCAAGUUGGAGGCUUUGUGUCAGCUGCAAAUCCUACCAGUUAUGUCCAAGAAUGGCUUUCCCUCGGGCAGGUGGCAGCGGCCAUCUCCCACUGGGAAUAUGGCGUAGUAUCUCCGGUCCAUUCCUUGGAUGCUAAGGACUGCGGGAAUGAGGGAGUCAGAUAAAGAACAAACCUCGAAACGAACAGUUAAAUUGAAAUGCUAUGUGCCUGACCCAAUGGUAGGCACAUAGUAGGCACUCAACUCAUAUGUUUAAUUGAAUUGAAAAUAUCCCUUAGGAAAAAAAAAAAACACACAAAAAACCACAAGAGCCCCAGCCAGUUUACUCCAGGUAGAUUUCCACAAUAUGCAAAGUGGUGGUGGGGUCAAGACAGAUGACACCAGCACUUUAAACUCUUUGUGUGGGUAUGCGUGGGUGUAUGUUUGGGAAGAAAAACAAAGGUGCAGACUAUCUUCCUUUUUUUCUUCUUCAGCCUCCAUCCCUGGCCUCCUCCCCUCACACACACUGGACUUGGUACAAAAUGUCGGUGUGGUCCUAGAUGAAGCAUUGGGGUGGGGGAGGGAGAGGGAGCUUUGUGUUAAGUGCCUACUGGAAAUGCACUGUGGGGUUUUUUCCUGUAUGGGAAACCAUUUAUGCCAAGCUUUUCCCCAUUUCCCAUAUUUAUCUCAUCUGGUUAGCUGCCUCUGCUUCCAGCUUUGUGUAAUUCUCUUUGCCAGCUGCACAAAGCUGAUUUUUUCCAAAGUCUAAAGACUGAGCUCACCUGGCUAGAUUGUUGUGUGUUUUGUUGAAUUUUUUCAUAAUGUAAUGCCGUAUUUAUUGUUUUUAAAAUGAAAGGAAUACUAAUAAGUCUUAAAAGUUCCUUCAUGCAUAAGAUUUUUUUCCAGUUACUGGGUUUAACUGGUGUACAUUAAUUAGAUGUCCAUACUGUAUUUUGUUUGCAUUAAGUAAUUUUCUUUUUGACUUAGUAUCCGGCACACAAAGUGGGUUAGUACUACAGUAUUUGCGUUACUUUAAGUACUAAGUAUGCAGGUUUCCUGGUACCAUUGAGUUGCUGCUAUUAAAGCUCACACACGAAAUGGCUAAAAGUUACAAGUGUGCAAAUUAUGACUGCGUGAGCCUUAGAAAAUAAAAUGUAUAAAGGGCAACACAUGAGCUGUCAAACAGUGUUAGGAGUGUGUUUAUAUGUACAGAGUUGUGCAUAGCAAUCGUUUUAUUUAAGUUGAUAUGUAGUCUACUCACAUUUUCAUUAUUUAGCAAUUUUGUACAAAAAUAGCAAUUAAUUUGUAAACACUGCCAGAAUACUUUCUAGCUGCUUUGUAAUUUUUUAAGAGUGUUAUUUUGUUUUUGUUUUUCUGUUCUUUGUUGUGGCUCUUGUUUUCAUUUUUGUUGUACGUGUAGAUCUGUAAAUAAAAUUGCAGUAUUUAAAGCUUAAGCUUUCAGGAAAAAGAAAAUAAGAAUUCAGUGUGUGCAUGACAACUCGUGUGUAUGAGAAGGAGGGAUAUGAAGGAAGAUGGCUUGCAGAGUAAGUCGGGUGGCAAUUGUCAGGGUGUGGGAAUUUCUUUUCCUACGGGGUACGUGAUUUUGUAAAAAGGAAGUAUUUCUCCCAAAAUUGGGAGUAGGCAAACUACUAAUCAGUUUAGCUUUGUGUUGUAUGCUAGUUUAAAAAAGAAAAUAUGUAAUAUAAUGUAAAAAAAAACAAAAAAAAGCUUUUAUGAUGGAUUUUGUAAAUAGAUUUGUUACAGGGUGACCUGUUCUCUAGCUGUGAUCUUACCACUUCAAAUGGGUGUAAUUUGAAUAAAUUUUGUAUGGUAAAGGAUCAAUAAAAUGAUUUUUUUUAAGAGUU